GGCUGCGCUCCGAGCUGCGGAGUCCGGGACUGGAGCUGCCCGGGCGGGUUCGCGCCCCGAAGGCUGAGAGCUGGCGCUGCUCGUGCCCUGUGUGCCAGACGGCGGAGCUCCGCGGCCGGACCCCGCGGCCCCGCUUUGCUGCCGACUGGAGUUUGGGGGAAGAAACUCUCCUGCGCCCCAGAGGAUUUCUUCCUCGGCGAAGGGACAGCGAAAGAUGAGGGUGGCAGGAAGAGAAGGGCGCUUUCUGUCUGCCGGGGUCGCAGCGCGAGAGGGCAGUGCCAUGUUCCUCUCCAUCCUAGUGGCGCUGUGCCUGUGGCUGCACCUGGCGCUGGGCGUGCGCGGCGCGCCCUGCGAGGCGGUGCGCAUCCCUAUGUGCCGGCACAUGCCCUGGAACAUCACGCGGAUGCCCAACCACCUGCACCACAGCACGCAGGAGAACGCCAUCCUGGCCAUCGAGCAGUACGAGGAGCUGGUGGACGUGAACUGCAGCGCCGUGCUGCGCUUCUUCCUCUGUGCCAUGUACGCGCCCAUUUGCACCCUGGAGUUCCUGCACGACCCUAUCAAGCCGUGCAAGUCGGUGUGCCAACGCGCGCGCGACGACUGCGAGCCCCUCAUGAAGAUGUACAACCACAGCUGGCCCGAAAGCCUGGCCUGCGACGAGCUGCCUGUCUAUGACCGUGGCGUGUGCAUCUCGCCUGAAGCCAUCGUCACGGACCUCCCGGAGGAUGUUAAGUGGAUAGACAUCACACCAGACAUGAUGGUACAGGAAAGGCCUCUUGAUGUUGACUGUAAACGCCUAAGCCCCGAUCGGUGCAAGUGUAAAAAGGUGAAGCCAACUUUGGCAACGUAUCUCAGCAAAAACUACAGCUAUGUUAUUCAUGCCAAAAUAAAAGCUGUGCAGAGGAGUGGCUGCAAUGAGGUCACAACGGUGGUGGAUGUAAAAGAGAUCUUCAAGUCCUCAUCACCCAUCCCUCGAACUCAAGUCCCGCUCAUUACAAAUUCUUCUUGCCAGUGUCCACACAUCCUGCCCCAUCAAGAUGUUCUCAUCAUGUGUUACGAGUGGCGCUCAAGGAUGAUGCUUCUUGAAAAUUGCUUAGUUGAAAAAUGGAGAGAUCAGCUUAGUAAAAGAUCCAUACAGUGGGAAGAGAGGCUGCAGGAACAGCGGAGAACAGUUCAGGACAAGAAGAAAACAGCCGGGCGCACCAGUCGUAGUAAUCCCCCCAAACCAAAGGGAAAGCCUCCUGCUCCCAAACCAGCCAGUCCCAAGAAGAACAUUAAAACUAGGAGUGCCCAGAAGAGAACAAACCCGAAAAGAGUGUGAGCUAACUAGUUUCCAAAGCGGAGACUUCCGACUUCCUUACAGGAUGAGGCUGGGCAUUGCCUGGGACAGCCUAUGUAAGGCCAUGUGCCCCUUGCCCUAACAACUCACUGCAGUGCUCUUCAUAGACACAUCUUGCAGCAUUUUUCUUAAGGCUAUGCUUCAGUUUUUCUUUGUAAGCCAUCACAAGCCAUAGUGGUAGGUUUGCCCUUUGGUACAGAAGGUGAGUUAAAGCUGGUGGAAAAGGCUUAUUGCAUUGCAUUCAGAGUAACCUGUGUGCAUACUCUAGAAGAGUAGGGAAAAUAAUGCUUGUUACAAUUCGACCUAAUAUGUGCAUUGUAAAAUAAAUGCCAUAUUUCAAACAAAACACGUAAUUUUUUUACAGUAUGUUUUAUUACCUUUUGAUAUCUGUUGUUGCAAUGUUAGUGAUGUUUUAAAAUGUGAUCGAAAAUAUAAUGCUUCUAAGAAGGAACAGUAGUGGAAUGAAUGUCUAAAAGAUCUUUAUGUGUUUAUGGUCUGCAGAAGGAUUUUUGUGAUGAAAGGGGAUUUUUUGAAAAAUCUAGAGAAGUAGCAUAUGGAAAACUAUAAUGUGUCUUUUUUACAAUGACUUCAGCUCUGUUUUUAGCUAGAAACUCUAAAAACAAAAAUAAUAAUAAAGAAAAAUAAAUAAAAAGGAGAGGCAGACAAUGUCUGGAUUCCUGUUUUUUGGUUACCUGAUUUCAUGAUCAUGAUGCUUCUUGUCAACACCCUCUUAAGCAGCACCAGAAACAGUGAGUUUGUCUGUACCAUUAGGAGUUAGGUACUAAUUAGUUGGCUAAUGCUCAAGUAUUUUAUACCCACAAGAGAGGUAUGUCACUCAUCUUACUUCCCAGGACAUCCACCCUGAGAAUAAUUUGACAAGCUUAAAAAUGGCCUUCAUGUGAGUGCCAAAUUUUGUUUUCUUCAUUUAAAUAUUUUCUUUGCCUAAAUACAUGUGAGAGGAGUUAAAUAUAAAUGUACAGAGAGGAAAGUUGAGGUUCCACCUCUGAAAUGAGAAUUACUUGACAGUUGGGAUACUUUAAUCAGAAAAAAAGAACUUAUCUUGCAGCAUUUUAUCAACAAAUUUCAUAAUUGUGGACAAUUGGAGGCAUUUAUUUUAAAAAACAAUUUUAUUGGCCUUUUGCUAACACAGUAAGCAUGUAUUCUCUAUAAGGCAUUCAAUAAAUGCACAACGCCCAAAGGAAAUAAAAUCCUAUCUAAUCCUACUCUCCACUACACAGAGGUAAUCACUAUUAGUAUUUUGGCAUAUUAUUCUCCAGGUGUUUCUUAUGCACUUAUAAAAUGAUUUGAACAAAUAAAACUAGGAACCUGCUAUACAUGUGUUUCAUAACCUGCCUCCUUUGCUUGGCCCUUUAUUGAGAUAAGUUUUCCUGUCAAGAAAGCAGAAACCAUCUCAUUUCUAACAGCUGUGUUAUAUUCCAUAGUAUGCAUUACUCAACAAACUGUUGUGCUAUUGGAUACUUAGGUGGUUUCUUCACUGACAAUACUGAAUAAACAUCUCAAUAGUCAAA